CCCGCGGCGGUUCGAAUUCUGUGCUGCCGGGGUUCGCUGGUUCUCCGAGUUGUGUCCGAGGCUUCCACGCGCAGGGGCCCGGGAAAGGGUCAGAGGCUUCCUAACGCAGACUCGAGUGCGAAGCGCGCAGUCGCCGGGUGGGUCUCUCCCCAGCGACGAUUUGGGUGAAAUGGAAUCUAGUUCAUCAGACUACUAUAAUAAAGACAAUGAAGAGGAAAGUUUGCUUGCAAAUGUUGCUUCCUUAAGACAUGAACUGAAGAUAACAGAAUGGAGUUUGCAGAGUUUAGGGGAAGAGUUAUCCAGUGUUAGUCCAAGUGAAAAUUCUGAUUAUGCCCCUAAUCCUUCAAGGUCUGAAAAGCUAAUUUUGGAUGUUCAGCCUAGCCACCCUGGACUUUUGAAUUAUUCACCUUAUGAAAACGUCUGUAAAAUAUCUGGUAGCAGCACUGAUUUUCAAAAAAAGCCAAGAGAUAAGAUGUUUUCAUCUUCUGCCCCUGUGGAUCAGGAGAUUAAAAGCCUUCGAGAGAAACUAAAUAAACUUAGGCAACAGAAUGCUUGUUUGGUCACACAGAAUCAUUCCUUAAUGACUAAAUUUGAAUCUAUUCACUUUGAAUUAACACAGUCAAGAGCAAAAGUUUCUAUGCUUGAGUCUGCUCAACAGCAGGCAGCCAGUGUCCCAAUCUUAGAAGAACAGAUUAUAAAUUUGGAAGCAGAGGUUUCAGCUCAAGAUAAAGUUUUGAGAGAGGCAGAAAAUAAGCUGGAACAGAGCCAGAAAAUGGUAAUUGAAAAGGAACAGAGUUUGCAGGAGUCCAAAGAGGAAUGUAUAAAAUUAAAGGUGGACUUACUUGAACAAACCAAACAAGGAAAAAGAGCUGAACGACAAAGGAAUGAAGCACUAUAUAAUGCCGAAGAGCUGAGUAAAGCUUUCCAACAAUAUAAAAAAAAAGUGGCUGAAAAACUGGAAAAGGUUCAAGCUGAAGAAGAAAUAUUAGAGAGAAAUCUAACUAACUGUGAAAAAGAAAAUAAAAGGCUACAAGAAAGGUGUGGUCUAUAUAAAAGUGAACUUGAAAUUCUGAAAGAGAAAUUAAGGCAGUUAAAAGAAGAAAAUAACAACGGAAAAGAAAAAUUAAGGAUCAUGGCAGUGAAAAAUUCAGAAGUCAUGGCACAACUAACUGAAUCUAGACAAAGUAUUUUGAAGCUAGAGAGUGAGUUAGAGAACAAAGACGAAAUACUUAGAGACAAAUUUUCUUUAAUGAAUGAAAACCGAGAAUUAAAGGUCCGUGUUGCAGCACAGAAUGAGCGACUAGAUUUAUGUCAACAAGAAAUUGAAAGUUCAAGGGUAGAACUAAGAAGUUUGGAAAAGAUUAUAUCCCAGUUGCCAAUGAGUAGCUUCUCAAACAAGGAAGACCGUUGCAUUGGCUGCUGUGAGGCAAAUAAAUUGGUGAUUUCGGAAUUGAGAAUUAAGCUUGCAAUAAAAGAGGCAGAAAUUCAAAAGCUUCAUGCAAACCUGACUGCAAAUCAGUUAUCUCAGAGUCUUAUUACUUGUAAUGACAGCCAAGAAAGUAGCAAAUUAAGUAGUUUAGAAACAGAACCUGUAAAGCUAGGUGGUCAUCAAGUAGCAGAAAGCGUAAAAGAUCAAAAUCAACAUACUAUGAACAAGCAAUAUGAAAAAGAGAGGCAAAGACUUGUUACUGGAAUAGAAGAACUACGUACUAAGCUGAUACAAAUAGAAGCUGAAAAUUCUGAUUUGAAGGUUAACAUGGCUCACAGAACUAGUCAGUUUCAGCUGAUUCAAGAGGAGCUGCUAGAGAAAGCUUCAAACUCCAGCAAACUGGAAAGUGAAAUGACAAAGAAAUGUUCUCAACUUUUAACUCUUGAGAAACAGCUGGAAGAAAAGAUAGUUGCUUAUUCCUCUAUUGCUGCAAAAAAUGCAGAACUAGAACAGGAGCUUAUGGAAAAGAAUGAAAAGAUAAGGAGUCUAGAAACCAAUAUUAAUACAGAGCAUGAGAAAAUUUGUUUAGCCUUUGAAAAAGCAAAGAAAAUUCACUUGGAACAGCAUAAAGAAAUGGAAAAGCAGAUUGAAAGACUUGAAGCUCAACUAGAGAAAAAGGACCAACAAUUUAAAGAACAAGAAAAGACUAUGUCCAUGUUGCAACAAGAUAUAAUAUGCAAACAACAUCAUCUUGAAUCACUAGAUAGACUCUUGACGGAAAGCAAAGGGGAAAUGAAAAAGGAAAAUAUGAAGAAAGAUGAAGCUUUAAAAGCAUUACAGAACCAAGUAUCUGAAGAAACAAUCAAGGUUAGGCAACUAGAUUCAGCAUUGGAAAUUUGUAAGGAAGAACUUGUCUUGCAUUUGAAUCAAUUGGAAGGAAAUAAGGAAAAGUUUGAAAAACAGUUAAAGAAGAAAUCUGAAGAGGUAUAUUGUUUACAGAAAGAGCUAAAGAUAAAAAAUCACAGUCUUCAAGAGACUUCUGAGCAAAACGUUAUUCUACAGCAUACUCUUCAGCAACAGCAGCAAAUGUUACAACAAGAGACAAUUAGAAAUGGAGAGCUAGAAGAUACUCAAACUAAACUUGAAAAACAGGUGUCAAAACUGGAACAAGAACUUCAAAAACAAAGGGAAAGUUCAGCUGAAAAGUUGAGAAAAAUGGAGGAGAAAUGUGAAUCAGCUGCACAUGAAGCAGAUUUGAAAAGGCAAAAAGUGAUUGAGCUUACUGGCACUGCCAGGCAAGUAAAGAUUGAGAUGGAUCAGUACAAAGAAGAGCUGUCUAAAAUGGAAAAGGAAAUAAUGCACCUAAAACGAGAUGGAGAAAAUAAAGCAAUGCACCUCUCUCAAUUAGAUAUGAUCUUAGAUCAGACAAAGACAGAGCUAGAAAAGAAAACAAAUGCUGUAAAGGAGUUAGAAAAGUUACAGCACAGUACUGAAACUGAACUAACAGAAGCCUUGCAAAAACGGGAAGUACUUGAGACUGAACUACAAAAUGCUCAUGGAGAAUUAAAAAGUACUUUAAGACAACUCCAGGAAUUGAGAGAUGUACUACAGAAGGCUCAAUUAUCAUUAGAGGAAAAAUACACUACUAUAAAGGAUCUCACAGCUGAACUUAGAGAAUGCAAGAUGGAGAUUGAAGACAAAAAGCAGGAGCUCCUUGAAAUGGAUCAGGCACUUAAAGAGAGAAAUUGGGAACUAAAGCAAAGAGCAGCUCAGGUUACACAUUUGGAUAUGACUAUUCGUGAGCACAGAGGAGAAAUGGAACAAAAAAUAAUUAAAUUAGAAGGUACUCUGGAGAAAUCAGAAUUGGAACUUAAAGAAUGUAACAAACAGGUUAUGAAAGAGCAAGAACAGUACAUUGCCACUCAGUACAAGGAGGCCAUAGAUUUGGGGCAAGAAUUGAGGCUGACCCGGGAGCAGGUGCAGAACUCUCAUACAGAAUUGGCAGAGGCUCGUCAUCAGCAAGUCCAAGCACAGAGAGAAAUAGAAAGGCUCUCUAGUGAACUGGAGGAUAUGAAGCAACUCUCUAAAGAGAAAGAUGCUCAUGGAAACCAUUUAGCUGAAGAACUGGGGGCUUCUAAAGUACGUGAAGCUCAUUUAGAAGCAAGAAUGCAAGCAGAAAUCAAGAAAUUGUCAGCAGAAGUAGAAUCUCUCAAAGAAGCUUAUCAUAUGGAGAUGAUUUCACAUCAAGAGAACCAUGCAAAGUGGAAGAUUUCUGCUGACUCUCAAAAGUCUUCUGUUCAGCAACUAAACGAACAGUUAGAGAAGGCAAAAUUGGAAUUAGAAGAAGCUCAGGAUACUGUAAGCAAUUUGCAUCAACAAGUCCAAGAUAGGAAUGAAGUAAUUGAAGCUGCAAAUGAAGCAUUACUUACUAAAGUAAGUAAACAUAUAAAAGUAAUAAAGCAUAUCUAUGAAAACAUAAAUGUCUGACUUAUUUACCUGUCUUAGUAGUUUAUAGAGGACUAUAUGACCAAAUAUUGGCCUGUUUGAAUAAAAACCAUUUGAUUUAGAAGAUGUUGAAUUUAGGAAAUUAUUAAGAUGAUGUACAUCUUAUUACCGUAGAAGAUAUAAUUUAUAAAUGUUCAAAUAUAAACUCAUCUAAUCAUAAUGUUUAGAGGGUUUUAUACUUGAUGUACCUAAAAAAAGGUAGAAACAUUUUUCAAAAUCAGCAAAGUUCUUUUAAAAUCAUAAAGUAGGCCGGGCGUGGUGGCUCACUCCUGUAUUCCCAGCACUUCAGGAGGCCGAGGUGGGCAGAUCACUUGAGGUCAACAAGGGCAAAGACAAUUUUUUGAGAGCCAUGAAGGCAUCAUUAUAUUAUGGCUCACUACAAUUACGUUCACAACAGUGACCUUCUUUGAGUCUUAAGAAAAAGUUGAAUUAAUUUAAUGUAUUCAGUGUACUAUAUUUAAUUGUAAAAGUUAUGUGUUAAACUGUAACUUAAAUAAAAUCCUACUUAUAUGAGAUACCACAUAUCAAUUAUGGCUAGAUAAUGCAGAAUAGGAAAAAGAAAAAGACUGCAGCUGUGUACAGUCCUAUUCUGUGCCAACUCUACAACUGUUUUGUUAAUUGUGAUUUUAAGAAUGUGAAUGUAGGAUUUACAACAAAAAAUUGGCACUCUAGCCACUUUAAACCAACAGGCUUUAAACCAACAAAGAUCAAAAGAGACCAAGAAGGCCAUUACAUAAUGGUAAAGGGAUCAAUUCAACAAGAAGAGCUAACUGUCCUAAAUAUAUAUGCACCCAAUACAGGAGCACCCAGAUUCAUAAGUCAAGUCCUUAGAGACCUACAAAGAGACUUAGACUCCCACACAAUAAUAAUGGGAGACUUUAACACCCCACUGUCAACAUUAGACAGAUCAACGAGACAGAAAAUCAACAAGGAUAUCCAGGACUUGAACUCAGCUCUGCACCAAGCAGACCUAAUAGACAUCGACAGAACUCUCCACUGCAAAUCAACAGAAUAUACAUUCUUCUCAGCACCAAAUCACACUUCUGCCAAAAUUGACCACAUAGUUGGAAAUAAAGCAUUCUUCAGCAAAUGUAAAAGAAUAGAAAUCACCACAAACUGUCUCUGAGACAACAGUGAAAUCAAAUUAGAACUCAGGAUUAAGAAACUCACUCAGAACCACACAACUCAUGAAAACUGAACAACCUCCUUCUGAAUGACUACUGGGUACAUAACGAAAUGAAGGCAGAAAUGAAGAUGUUCUUUGAAACCAAUGAGAACAAAGACACAACAUACCAGAAUCUCUGGGACACAUUUAAAGCAGUGUGGAGAGGGAAAUUUAUAGCACUAAAUGCCCACAAGAGAAAGCAGGAAAGAUCUAAAAUUGACAUCCUGACAUCACAAUUAAAAGAGCUAGAGAAGCAAGAGCAAACACAUUCAAAAGCUAGCAGAAGGCAAGAAAUAAGUAAGAUCAGAGCAGAACUGAAGGAGAUAGAGACACAAAAAACCCUUCAAAAAAUCAAUGAAUCCAGGAGCUGGUUUUUAGAAAAGAUCAACAAAAUUGAUAGACCGCUAGCAAGACUAAUAAAGAAGAAAAGAGAGAAGAAUCAAAUAGAGGCAAUAAAAAAUGAUAAAGAGGAUAUCACCACUGAUCCCAUAGAAAUACAAACUACCAUCAGAGAAUACUAUAAACACCUCUACACAAAUAAACUAGAAAACCUAGAAGAAAUGGAUAAAGUCCUCGACACAUACACCCUCCCAAGACUAAACCAGGAAGAAGUUGAAUCCCUGAGUAGACCAACAACAGGUUCUGAAAUUGAGGCAGUAAUUAAUAGCCUACCAACCAAAAAAAGUCCAGGACCAGACAGAUUCAUAGCUGAAUUCUACCAGAGGUACAAAGAGGAGCUGGUACCAUUCCUUCUGAAACUAUUCUAAUCAAUAGAAAAAGAGAGAAUCCUCCCUAACUCAUUUUCUGAGGCCAGCAUCAUCCUGAUACCAAGGCCUGGCAGAGACGCAACAAAAAAAGAGAAUUUUAGACCAAUAUCCCUGAUGAACAUCGAUGCAAAAAUCCUCAAUAAAAUACUGGCAAACCGAAUCCAGCAGCACAUCAAAAAGCUUAUCCACCACAAUUAAGUUGGCUUCAUCCCUGGGAUGCAUGGCUGGUUCAACAUACGCAAAUCAAUAAAUGUAAUCCAUCACAUGAACCAAACCAAAGACAAAAACCACAUGAUUAUCUCAAUAGAUGCAGAAAAGGCUUUCAACAAAAUUCAACAGCCCUUCAUGCUAAAAACUCUCAAACUAGGUAUUGAUGGGACAUAUCUCAAAAUAAUAAGAGCUAUUUAUUACAAACCCACAGCCAAUAUCAUACUGAAUGGGCAAAAACUGGAAGCAUUCCCUUUGAAAACUGGCACAAGACAGGGGUGCCCUCUCUCACCACUCCUAUUCAACAUAGUGUUGGAAGUUCUGGCCAGGGCAAUCAGGCAGGAGAAAGAAAGAAAGGGUAUUCAAUUAGGAAAAGAGGAAGUCAAACUGUCCCUGUUUGCAGAUGACAUGAUUGUAUAUUUAGAAAACCCUAUCAUCUCAGCCCCAAAUCUCCUUAAGCUGAUAACUUCAGCAAAGUCUCAGGAUACAAAAUCAAUGUGCAAAAAUAACAAGCAUUCUUAUACACCAAUAACCGACCAACAGAGAGCCAAAUUAUGAGUGAACUCCCAUUCACAAUUGCUUCAAAGAGAAUAAAAUACCUAGGAAUCCAACUUACAAGGGAUGUGAAGGAUCUCCAAGGAGAACUACAAACCACUGCUCAAUGAAAUAAAAGAGGACACAAACAAAUGGGAGAACAUUCCAUGCUCAUGGAUAGGAAGAAUCAAUAUAAUGAAAAUGGCCAUACUGCCCAAGGUAAUUUAUAGAUUCAAUGCCAUCUCCAUCAAGCUGCCAAUUACUUUCUUCACAAAACUGGAAAACAACUACCUUAAAGUUCAUAUGGAACCAAAAAAGAGCCCACACAGCCAAGACAAUCCUAAGCCAAAAGAAAAAAGCUGGAGGCAUCACGCUUCCUGACUACAGGGCUACAGUAACCAAAACAGCAUGGUACUGGUACCAAAACAGAGAUAUAGACCAAUGGAACACAACAGAUCCCUCAGAAAUAACACCACACAUCUACAACCAUCUGAUCUUUGACAAACCUGACAAAAACAAGAAAUGGGGAAAGGAUUCCCUAUUUAAUAAAUGGUGCUGGAAAAACUGGCUAGCCAUAUGUAGAAAGGUGAAACUGGAUCCCUUCCUUACACCUUAUACAAAAAUUAAUUCAAGAUGGAUUAAAGACUUAAAUGUUAGACCUAAAACUAUAAAAACCCUAGAAGAAAACCUAGGCAAUACCAUUGCCUAGGCAUGGGCAUAGGCAUGGGCAAGGACUUCAUGACUGAAACACCAAAAGAAAUGGCAACAAAAACCAAAAUAGACAAAUGGGAUCUAAUUAAAGAGCUUCUGCACAGCAAAAGAAACUACCAUCAGAGUGAACAGGCAACCUACAGAAUGGGAGAAAAUUUUUGCAAUCUACUCAUCUGACAAAGGGCUAAUAUCCAGAAUCUACAAAGAACUUAAACAAAUUUACAAGAAAAAAACAACCCCAUCAAAAAGUGGGAGAAGGAUAUGAACAGACACUUCUCAAAAGAAGACAUUUAUGCAGCCAACAGACACAUGAAAAAAUGUUCAUCAUCACUGGUCAUCAGAGAAAUGCAAAUCAAAACCACAAUGAGAUACCAUCUCACACCAGUUAGAAUGGUGAUCAUUAAAAAGUCAGGAAACAACAGGUGCUGGAGAGGAUGUGGAGAACUAGGAACACUUUUACACUGUUGGUGGGACUGUAAACUAGUUCAACCAUUGUGGAAGACAGUGUGGCGAUUCCUCAAGGAUCUAGAACUAGAAAUACCAUUUGACCCAGCCAUCCCAUUACUGGGUAUAUACCCAAAGUACUAUAAAUCAUGCUGCUAUAAAGACACAUGCACAUGUAUGUUUAUUGCGGCACUAUUCACAAUAGGAAAGACUUGGAACCAACCCAAAUGUCCAUCAGUGAUAGACUAGAUUCAGAAAAUGUGGCACAUAUACACCAUGGAAUACUAUGCAGCCAUAAAAAAGGAUGAGUUCAUGUCCUUUGUAGGGACAUGGAUAAAGCUGGAAACCAUCAUCCUGAGCAAACUAUUGCAAGGACAAAAAACCAAACACCGCAUGUUCUCACUCAUAGGUGGAAAUCGAACAAUGAGAACACUUGGACACAGGGUGGGGAACAUCACACACUGGGGCCUGUUGUGGGGUGGGGGGAGGGGGGAGGGAUAGCAUUAAGAGAAAUCCCUAAUGUAAAUGACGAGUUAAUGGGUGCAGCACACCAACAUGGCACAUGUAUACAUAUGUAACAAACCUGCACGUUGAGUACAUGUACCCUAGAACUUAAAGUAUUUUUAAAAAAUCAUAUAAAUCAAUUUUAGAUGAAGUAGUAAAAAAAAAAAAAAAGGAAAAUACCAAAAUAUGCGUGUUAAACUUUUAUUUUGUAAUGCAUUCUGUGGUUAUGACAGUUUUAGUUAUGAACACAGUAUUUUUGAAAGCUACUUUAAGAAUAGAAACUAUCAGAGUAAAACUGACAGGAUUUAGAAAUAUAUAUCUUAUGGAUACCUUUAAGAAAAGGCAAAUGUAUUUGAAGAGGAGACUACUAUACUUACAUUAUUAAGCUUUUGAAAUUAAAAUAUCAUCUCUUUUUUUAGGCUUUUUGGUUUUUUAGUGUAUGUAGUCUCAUUCCUAGGAUCCCAAAGUUCAGUCAGAGGACCCAAAUGAAAGACAUGAAAAAAAUUGAAAUGAAAAGUUUAUUUAACAAGGAUUGAUUUAUUAAAAAUUUAUCACUUUAAGUUUUUGAAAAAUUUCUAAUGCACUAAAGCUUUCUUGUAAUGAGAACACAAAAAGCAGAAUAGCUUAUCUAUUUAUUCCCUACUGGAAAUUCUGAAAGGGGUCUUUUUGUGUCUAUAUGUGUUAGAUUAACAAAAGAUAGCGUACCUCUACAUCUUUGCAGAGAAAUUUUUAGGUGUAAGAUUUCAAUCUUGAAUAGAAAUUGAUAUUGUCAUUAACACCAAAAAUAUAUAUAUAAGGAGAAUCUAGUUUUAAUGGAAUUUCUUAGAAUAAGCAUAUUUCAAAGGAAUAUGUGUAAUUUUCCCAAAGUGAACCUAUCUUAAGUAAAGGUUUUAAACAGAGCUUGGAAAACUCUCAAGAAUUAUAAACAGAAUUCCUAUAGUGGGACAAAGGUUGACUUUCUAAAAGUCUAUGAUUUUCUAAGGAGUUCAUUCAUUUAACAAAAAUGUAUUGAGCACCUACUAUGUACCAAUUUAUCUGCAGGAAUCAGAAUUAACCAGAUUACAGGCCAAAAUUUCUGGACAUGAAAAGGCAGAAGACAUCAAGUUUCUGCCAGCCCCAUUUACAUCUCCAACAGAAAUUAUGCCUGAUGUUCAAGAUCCAAAAUUUGCUAAAUGUUUUCACACAUCUUUUUCCAAGUGUACAAAAUUACGUCGCUCUAUUAGUGCCAGUGAUCUUACUUUCAAAAUUCAUGGUGAUGAAGAUCUUUCUGAAGAAUUACUACAGGACUUAAAGAAAAUGCAAUUAGAACAGCCUUCAACAUUAGAAGAAAGCCAUAAGAAUCUGACUUACACCCAGCCAGACUCAUUUAAACCUCUCACAUAUAACCUAGAAGCUGAUAGUUCUGAGAAUAAUGACUUUAACACGCUUAGUGGGAUGCUAAGAUACAUAAACAAAGAAGUAAGACUAUUAAAAAAGUCUUCUAUGCAAACAGGUGCUGGUUUAAAUCAGGUAUGUAUUUUAUACACUGUAAACUGUAAUAAUUUGUUUCCAAAGAAUAUCAUUUUAUUACUUGGAAGAAAAUUCAUAUAUUUAAAUGAAAAACUACUAAUAUUUGAAGAAGGAAGAUUUUACAUUUUAUACAUUAAGUAAAAUCAAUACCAAAAGACAUUUUCUCUAUUGCAUGGUGUGAGACAAUACGGGGAAAGAGAGAGGCAGAGGGAGACAGAACAGGAAGUAGAACGAAAAAUAGGAAGAUAGACAUGAAAGUGCUUAAAAAUAAAAAAAUUAAAAAACUGAAAAAAAGAAAAAUGGUAAGAAAUAUGCAGUGAGAGGAAUCCAGAGAAAGUAGGUUCUGAGGUGAAUGUUCUCAUAACUUCGUCAUAAUUUACUGUUCAUUUGGGCUCUGUAUGUCAAAAUAAGUUAUUGCUGGCUAUCACUGAUCCUUGGAAAGUUGAUUUACUGAAUUAGCCAUUAUUUAAAAGCAUGAAUAAGGCCAACUGUCCUCAUCCUUAUAAUUUUUCACCCUAAAAUAUUUAUAUUCAUCUUUCCUUCUUUUGUCCCUUUUCUCUUUAAAAGAAAGAUAUAUCCCUCUUCUUUUUUAGAGAGAAAUUCUUGAACAUGUACUUUCAAGCCUUUAAUAUGCUUGCCUGUUUUGCUUCUCUGCUUCCUGAUUUAAUCUGUAUCUUCAGGCUUCUUUAUUUCCCUCUUCCUUUCAUUUCCAGACAUCUUAAAUUCAUACCCACUCUAAGCUGGGUGCAGUGGCACAUGCCUGCAAUCCCAGCUAUCCAGGAGGCUGAGGCAGGAGGAUUAUUUGAGCCCAGGAGUUUGAGACAAGUAUGGGCAACAUGGAGACCCCAUCUCAAAAAAAAUUUUUAUUCAUUCUAUUUCUCCAUUGUUGCUACCUCCUUACUACCCUUCCCACUUUGUAACUUACUGUAUUUGUCUCUUGAAUAUUAAAUUUACUGUUUUCUUGAAAGUCACAAAAAACUCUUUGUAUAAUAAACAAAUUUAGUAUCCUCUUUUUCUUCAGCUUUUGUAGAUUUAACUGUCCAUUCCCCCUUUUGAUAUUUUCUCUUCUCUUGACUUUUAUGAUUUAAUAUUUUUCUGGUCCUCUUCUUAUUUUGAACUAAUUACUUUCUCACUUUUCUGCUCCUCGUAUUCCUUAUGUUCCACAAUAUAGGAUUUAAUCUGUAGUUUGAGAAUGGAAAUAAUCUCCUUUAGAUAAUGUCAGCUUUUUAAAAAAUGCCUAACAUCAUUUUCAAACACAUCAAGAUAGCUUUGGUGGCCUGAACAGUUAAAAACUAUUUUUUUGGAAUAGAUCCAAGACAAAGAAAAAUUGUUGAGUGAGUUUUUCUUCAUAAUACUUAUUUUUGCUGGCUUAAGUAUAUGUCUAUCUACUUGUUUAUUGAUUGUCUCCCCCACUGAAAAUGUAAGCUCUGUGUGGAGAGGGUAUGGUCAUUUCGCUUAUUUCUAUAUUUCUAGUGCCUGGUAUAUAGUAGAUGCUGAAUGAAUAUUUAUGAAUGUAUCAAGUGGCUAAAUAAAUUAUAUACAGUAAACACAA